GUGACACUUCAUCCAAUCAGACGUGAAGCUGGCCCGAGACGUGGAGCCAUGCUGCGUACCGAAGUGCCCCGGCUUCCCCGGUCCACAACCGCCAUUGUCUGGUCGUGCCAUCUAAUGGCCACUGCCUCCGCCAUGGCUGGACCUUCCUCUGAGACGACCUCUGAGGAACAGCUGAUCACCCAGGAGCCCAAAGAGGCCAACUCCACUACGUCCCAGAAGCAGAGCAAGCAGAGGAAGCGAGGGCGCCAUGGGCCCCGCAGGUGCCACUCCAACUGCCGCGGGGACAGCUUCGCCACCUAUUUCCGCCGGGUGCUGAAGCAGGUUCACCAGGGCCUCAGCCUUUCCCGGGAGGCCGUGAGUGUCAUGGAUUCUUUGGUUCAUGACAUAUUGGACCGCAUCGCCACCGAGGCUGGUCACCUGGCCCGCUCCACCAAGCGCCAGACCAUCACUGCCUGGGAGACCCGGAUGGCUGUGCGCCUGCUGCUGCCGGGGCAGAUGGGCAAGCUCGCCGAGUCCGAAGGCACGAAGGCUGUCCUCAGAACUUCACUGUAUGCCAUACAGCAACAGAGAAAGUGAAUACGCUGAUACAAGAAGCAAGAAUAUUAGAAAAAUGUCAUGAAAAUAGUUGAAGAGAAAUGCUCACUGCACAAGGAGACCAAGAAAAACCCCCCACGAAAUCAGCCACAACUAAAUCGCUCUGGACGGUGCCGCCAGGUGACCCUACAUGUCCGGAGCAACACUUUGAAAACCAAAGACGCUUGGCAGAACCCUGUUCCUUUCCAGAGACAGAGCUGUGUACCUUGUCUAAAACACCGCAUCUCACUCAGUGACUUAUUUCUCAUUAUGCUAAUUGUUUUCGCUUUAAAGCGCCAGUCUUUCUGUCAAAUGGGACAUACAAAUAAAUUUCUAAAAUUA